GUCAGCUUCAGGCAUCGCGAGGCGUGGCGGCCCCAUGGCCCCGCUGGGAGGCGCCCCGCGGCUGGUACUGCUGUUCAGCGGCAAGAGGAAAUCCGGGAAGGACUUCGUGACCGAGGCGCUGCAGAGCAGGUGUCCGUGAGGCGGGAAAGGUGGAAGGGGGAGCUCUCCGCAUCACGUGACACGAGGAGUGCUUUUGGGUGUCACGGAGUGAGCUUUGGAGUACGGGUCGUCCGUUUGCAAGGCAGGAGGAGCACUGGGCUGGGGAAGGUGGAAUGCCACCAUUACAUAAAACAGUAGUCUACACAGGCGAGCCUCAAAGAAGCAGACUUGGAGCUGAUGUCUGUGCUGUCCUCCGGCUCUCUGGUCCACUCAAGGAACAGUAUGCUCAGGAGCAUGGCUUGAACUUCCAGAGACUCCUGGACACCAGCACCUACAAGGAGGCCUUUCGGAAGGACAUGAUCCGCUGGGGAGAGGAGAAACGCCAGGCUGACCCAGGCUUCUUUUGCAGGAAGAUUGUGGAGGGCAUCUCCCAGCCCAUCUGGCUGGUGAGUGACACACGGAGAGUGUCUGACAUCCAGUGGUUUCGGGAGGCCUAUGGGGCCGUGACGCAGACGGUCCGCGUUGUAGCGUUGGAGCAGAGCCGACAGCAGCGGGGCUGGGUGUUCACGCCAGGGGUGGACGAUGCUGAGUCAGAAUGUGGCCUGGACAACUUCGGGGACUUUGACUGGGUCAUCGAGAACCAUGGAGUUGAACAGCGCCUGGAGGAGCAGUUGGAGAACCUGAUAGAAUUUAUCCGCUCCAGACUUUAGUCACUAGGUUCUAGGAGUGAGCUGGGGCCUGCUGAGGUGGGGGUGGGGCUGACUCUGCAAAAUGGGGGUGUCCCCCGAUCCUGGCCGAGGUGAGGAACAGACAGGGGGGGUCUAGAUUCUGAGGGGGUUGGUGGAUAUUGGGCAAGGCAGGAAACCUCUGGAGACCUCAUUUUCUCCAUGGGGAAGACAGCCAUGCUCUUCAGGAGGAGACUCCAAGGGCAAAGGAGGGUGUCUUGGCUGUGCUUGAAGGCGAAACCCUGCCAUAUCCCCAGUGCCAGUCCCCUCAGCCUGUGGUGGCCUUGCAUCCUGACUGGAUGUUCUCAGCCCCUUGUUCUGGGCAAGAACCCAGAGCUCCCCAGUGUGGAUACUAAUAAACCUCUUGGAGCACA